ACAGACCCGGAAGCGGAUGGCGUGGACUGAAAGUUGCACGGCGGCGUGUGCGUUUCCUAGUUGUCUGGUGCUGCUAUAUAGGGGACGUGGGGUCCCCACAGACCUGCAGGUUCCGGCCCCUCUUUUCUCAACCCAGAGCAAAUUGAAACGUCCGGGUAACACACCGCUGUGCCACGGUUUUGGCGAGGGCUGACAAUUGUGAGCUGUAGAAGUACCAGCCUAACAACUGUUCAAGUGACUCCUGACCUAGAUGGGUGGUUUCAUGCACCUCCAGUACAACUGUGGCUCCUAGCAGCUGUGGCACAGGAUUUCCAAAGACUCAUGUUACGUGAGGAAGCCACCAAGAAGAGCAAAGAAAAGGAGCCAGGGAUGGCUCUUCCUCAGGGACGCUUGACUUUCAGGGAUGUGGCUAUAGAGUUCUCUUUGGAGGAGUGGAAAUGCCUGAACCCUGCACAGAGGGCUUUAUACAGGGCUGUGAUGUUGGAGAACUACAGGAACCUGGAGUUUGUGGAUAGCUCUUUAAAAUCCAUGAUGGAGUUCUCAUCAACCAGGCACAGUAUUACAGGAGAAGUGAUCCACACAGGGACGUUGCAAAGACAUAAAAGUCAUCACAUUGGAGAUUUUUGCUUCCCAGAAAUGAAGAAAGAUAUUCAUCACUUUGAGUUUCAGUGGCAAGAAGUUGAAAGAAAUGGCCAUGAAGCACCCAUGACAAAAAUCAAAAAGUUGACUGGUAGUACAGACCGAAGUGAUCACAGGCAUGCUGGAAACAAGCCUAUUAAAGAUCAGCUUGGAUUAAGCUUUCAUUCGCAUCUGCCUGAACUCCACAUGUUUCAGACUAAAGGGAAAAUUAGUAACCAAUUGGACAAGUCUAUCGGUGCUUCCUCAGCUUCAGAAUCCCAAAGAAUUUCUUGUAGGCUCAAAACUCAUAUUUCUAAUAAGUAUGGGAAGAAUUUCCUCCAUUCUUCAUUCACACAAAUACAGGAAAUAUGCAUGAGAGAAAAACCUUGCCAAAGUAAUGAGUGUGGCAAAGCCUUUAAUUAUAGCUCACUCUUAAGGAGACACCACAUAACCCAUUCAAGAGAGAGAGAAUAUAAAUGUGAUGUAUGUGGCAAGAUCUUUAAUCAGAAGCAAUACAUUGUAUAUCAUCAUAGAUGUCACACUGGUGAGAAAACUUACAAGUGUAAUGAGUGUGGGAAGACCUUCACUCAGAUGUCAUCCCUUGUAUGCCAUCGUAGACUUCAUACUGGAGAGAAACCUUACAAGUGUAAUGAGUGUGGCAAGACCUUCAGUGAGAAGUCAUCCCUUAGAUGCCAUCGUAGACUUCAUACUGGAGAGAAACCUUACAAGUGUAAUGAGUGUGGCAAGACUUUUGGUCGAAAUUCAGCCCUUGUAAUUCAUAAGGCAAUUCAUACUGGAGAGAAACCUUACAAGUGUAAUGAGUGUGGCAAGACCUUCAGUCAGAAAUCAUCCCUUCAAUGCCAUCAUAUACUUCACACUGGAGAGAAACCUUACAAAUGUGAAGAAUGUGACAAUGUUUACAUUCGCAGAUCACACCUUGAAAGACAUAGGAAGAUUCAUACUGGAGAGGGAUCAUACAAAUGUAAGGUUUGUGACAAGGUUUUCCGGAGUGAUUCAUACCUUGCAGAACAUCAGAGAGUUCAUACUGGAGAGAAACCAUACAAGUGUAAUAAAUGUGGCAGGAGUUUCAGUCGGAAGUCAUCCCUUCAAUACCAUCAUACACUUCACACUGGAGAGAAACCUUACACAUGUAAUGAAUGUGGCAAGGUUUUUAGUCGAAGAGAAAACCUUGCACGUCAUCAUAGACUUCAUGCUGGAGAGAAACCUUACAAAUGUGAAGAAUGUGACAAAGUUUUCAGUCGCAGAUCACACCUUGAAAGACAUAGGAGAAUUCAUACUGGGGAAAAACCAUACAAAUGUAAGGUUUGUGACAAGGCUUUCCGGAGUGAUUCAUGCCUUGCAAACCAUACGAGAGUUCAUACUGGAGAGAAACCUUACAAGUGUAAUAAAUGUGCGAAGGUUUUUAAUCAAAAAGGAAUCCUUGCACAACAUCAGAGAGUUCAUACUGGAGAGAAACCUUACAAGUGUAAUGAAUGUGGCAAGGUUUUUAAUCAAAAAGCAAGCCUUGCAAAACAUCAGAGAGUUCAUACUGCAGAGAAACCUUACAAGUGUAAUGAGUGUGGCAAAGCCUUUACUGGACAGUCAACACUUAUUCACCAUCAAGCAAUCCAUGGGUGUAGGGAAACUUUACAAAUGUAAUGAUUGUCACAAAGUCUUCAGUAAUGCUACAACCAUUGCAAAUCAUUACAGAAUCCAUAUUGAAGAGAGAUCUACAAGUGUAAUAAAUGUGGCAAAUUUUUCAGACGUCAUUCAUAACUUGUAGUUCAUCAGUGAACUCAUACUGGAGAGAAACCUUACAAAUAUCAUGACUGUGACAAGGUCUUCAGUCAAGCUUCAUCCUAUGCAAAACAUAGAAUUCAUACAGGAGAGAAACCUCACAAGUGUGAUGAUUGUGGCAAAGCCUUUACUUCAUGUUCACACCUCAUUAGACAUCAGAGAAUUCAUACUGGACAGAUGCCUUACAAAUGUAAGGGUGGCAAGGUCUUCACUCUGUGGUCAUUCCAUGCAGAACAUCAGAAAAUUCAUUUUUGAGAUAAUUGUUCCAAAUAAAAUGAAUAUAAAAAAUCAUAAAA